AGAGCCUCGGGCGCGGCGGGAGCGCAGUUAGAGCCGAUCUCCCGCGCCCCGAGGUUGCUCCUCUCCGAGGUCUCCCGCGGCCCAAGUUCUCCGCGCCCCGAGGUCUCCGCGCCCCGAGGUCUCCGCGGCCCGAGGUCUCCGCCCGCACCAUGCGGCUGGGCAGUCCUGGACUGCUCUUCCUGCUCUUCAGCAGCCUUCGAGCUGAUACUCAGGAGAAGGAAGUCAGAGCGAUGGUAGGCAGCGACGUGGAGCUCAGCUGCGCUUGCCCUGAAGGAAGCCGUUUUGAUUUAAAUGAUGUUUACGUAUAUUGGCAAACCAGUGAGUCGAAAACCGUGGUGACCUACCACAUCCCACAGAACAGCUCCUUGGAAAACGUGGACAGCCGCUACCGGAACCGAGCCCUGAUGUCACCGGCCGGCAUGCUGCGGGGCGACUUCUCCCUGCGCUUGUUCAACGUCACCCCCCAGGACGAGCAGAAGUUUCACUGCCUGGUGUUGAGCCAAUCCCUGGGAUUCCAGGAGGUUUUGAGCGUUGAGGUUACACUGCAUGUGGCAGCAAACUUCAGCGUGCCCGUCGUCAGCGCCCCCCACAGCCCCUCCCAGGAUGAGCUCACCUUCACGUGUACAUCCAUAAACGGCUACCCCAGGCCCAACGUGUACUGGAUCAAUAAGACGGACAACAGCCUGCUGGACCAGGCUCUGCAGAAUGACACCGUCUUCUUGAACAUGCGGGGCUUGUAUGACGUGGUCAGCGUGCUGAGGAUCGCACGGACCCCCAGCGUGAACAUUGGCUGCUGCAUAGAGAACGUGCUUCUGCAGCAGAACCUGACUGUCGGCAGCCAGACAGGAAAUGACAUCGGAGAGAGAGACAAGAUCACAGAGAAUCCAGUCAGUACCGGCGAGAAAAACGCGGCCACGUGGAGCAUCCUGGCUGUCCUGUGCCUGCUUGUGGUCGUGGCGGUGGCCAUAGGCUGGGUGUGCAGGGACCGAUGCCUCCAACACAGCUAUGCAGGUGCCUGGGCUGUGAGUCCGGAGACAGAGCUCACUGGUGAGUUUGCCGUGGGAAGCAGCAGGUUCUGGGGGGCCCAGGGGAGGCUUGGCUGCCAGCUGUCUUUCAGAGUUUCAAAAAACUUUCAGAAGGCAGAAGUCCCUUGCCUUGAACAACUGUUGUUCCUGGAGACGCAGCGAAGCCCUCGAUGGUGCGCACGGCAUUUCCUGCAGCCUCCCCUUGGCAUGGGAUGGCAUCCUGGUGUGCACUUUGUCACACUGCGAUGGGAUUUUCCCAACAUGCACAGAAGCAGAGAGACGAGUGCUAGACUCCCGCGCUCCCCAGUGCCCAGCCCCGACCAGGGUGUCCAGGGCGGGUCCAGGCACCGGCGCCCAGCCCCCAUGGGGUGUCCGGAGUGGGUCCAGGCACCGGCGCCCAGCCCCCGUGGGGUGUCCAGGGCGGGUCCAGGCACCGGCGCCCAGCCCCCGUGGGGUGUCCAGGGCGGGUCCAGGCACCGGCGCCCAGCCCCCAUGGGGUGUCCGGAGUGGGUCCAGGCACCGGCGCCCAGCCCCCGUGGGGUGUGCAGGGCGGGUCCAGGCACCGGCGCCCAGCCCCUGUGGGGUGUCCGGAGCGGGUCCGGGCACCGCCAGCUUCUCUCUGUGGCAGCCACUCCUGCAGCUCUCGUUUGCCCCUCAGUUCCAGGAGCAACAUAGAUGUGGAUUCCUGUCCAAUUUGGGAAAAAUGUCCACACACGGUCACCCACCUGGCAGGUGCCUCUGGCUGCAAGGGGCGCUGGGCUUCGCAGGCAGGCCAGCCGGGCUCCCCGCCAUGGGCCAGGAUCCCCUCCGAGCCCUGUUUGCCGCCCAGGAGAAGGGGUUCCCCGGGGACAGUGGGCUCAGGGUGUGCGCAGCCACCACGCUGUGGUGUCACCUGUGGACCCAGGCGAGCUGAUGGCCGACCGCAGAAACGCACUUCCAAGGCCAGGUCGGCCCAUCCAGAUGAUGCAGGAACACAGCUUGCUAAAAACACGGCCGGCCUGUUCCCGUCGGAGCCAGUCGAAGUUCCCUGAACAGGCCGCUGUUUCCGAAGCUUUAAACCCUGUGUUUCCACCAAGCUGAGUCCUGAGAAAACCGGCGUCUGCCUGCAGAAGGGAAAGGGGUGCUUCAUGUUCCUCUCUCUCCUUCAUCUCCCUUCCAAGGCCACGUUUGACCGGAGCUCACCGCCCAGAGCGUGGACAGGGCUUCCGUGAGACGCCACCGUGAGAGGCCAGGUGGCAGCUUGAGCAUGGACUCCCAGACUGCAGGGGAGCACUUGGGGCAGCCCCCAGAAGGACCACUGCUGGAUCCCAGGGAGAACCUGCUGGCGUUGGCUGUGAUCCUGGAAUGAGGCCCUUUCAAAAGCGUCAUCCACACCAAAGGCAAAUGUCCCCAAGUGAGUGGGCUCCCCGCUGUCACUGCCAGUCACCCACAGGAAGGGACUGGUGAUGGGCUGUCUCUACCCGGAGCGUGCGGGAUUCAGCACCAGGCUCUUCCCAGUACCCCAGACCCACUGUGGGUCUUCCCGUGGGAUGCGGGAUCCUGAGACCGAAGGGUGUUUGGUUUAAAAAGAAGACUGGGCGUCCGCUCUUCCAGGACGGCCUCUGUGCUGCUGGGGUCACGCGAGGCUGUUUGCAGGGGACACGGUCACAGGAGCUCUUCUGCCCUGAACGCUCCCAACCUGCCUCCCGCCCGGAAGCCACAGGACCCACUCAUGUGUGUGCCCACAAGUGUAGUUAGCCGUCCACACCGAGGAGCCCCCGGAAGUCCCCACUGGGCUUCAGUGUCCUCUGCCACAUUCCCUGGGAGGAACAAUGUCCCUCGGCUGUUCCGGUGAAAAGUUGAGCCACCUUUGGAAGACGCACGGGUGGAGUUUGCCAGAAGAAAGGCUGUGCCAGGGCCGUGUUUGGCUACAGGGGCUGCCGGGGCUCUUGGCUCUGCAGCGAGAAAGACACAGCCCAGCAGGGCUGGAGACGCCCAUGUCCAGCAGGCGCAGGCCUGGCAACACGGUCCCCAGAGUCCUGAGCAGCAGUUAGGUGCAUGGAGAGGGUAUCACCUGGUGGCCACAGUCCCCCUUCUCACCUCAGCAAUGAUCCCCAAAGUGAGAGGUGGCUCCCCCGGCCCCCACCACCCUCAGCAGCCCCACCCCACUCAACCCUGAGGGUCCCCAGGGUCCUGAUGAAGACCUCCGACCCCAGCGCCAGGCUCCUCGGAGCCCAACAGUCCCAAGGGGGCAGUGCUGAGGGGUACAGCCCUGGGCCCUGACCAGCCCCGGCACCUGCCAUGCUGGUUCCCGGAAUGAAUCAGCUGCUGACUGUCUCCAGAAGGGCUGGAAAGGAUGCUGCCAGGUGACCCGAGGUGCACUCGCCCCAGGGAGAUGGAGUAGACAGCCUGGCCUGGCCCUCGGGACACAUUGUCUGCCCCGGGGCUAUGGGCAAAUGCCCCUCCUUCUUACUUCCCAGAAUCCCCUGACAUUCCCAGGGUCAGCCAGGACCUGUUACAGCCCUGGUCACUUGGAACUGACAGCUGUGUGAGGCCUGCACUUCUCAGACCCAGACUUAGAACAAAAGGAGGAGUGAGGACUCAAGGCUACAAUGAGGUUCCAGUACUUGUUACAAGAAAUUGGUUUUCUGCAAAAAAAGUCCCUACCUGGGCCUUUAGGUGAAUGUGGGAUCCACUCCCGCUUUUAACAUGAAAGCAUUAGAAGAUGUGUGGUGUUUAUAAAAGAACAGUUGUCAUCACCGGGCAUUGAUUGGCAGGGACAAGGAGCUGCUUGGGUGUGGAAAGUUGGGGCGUUGGAAAGUGGGCUGUGGUGCCCAUUUGCAGUGACUGUGAAGUGACUCCAGGACGGACCUGCGGGGGCACCCAGAGAUCCUAAGCCCCAGGACUGAGGGUCGUGCAUCACCACUCGGGUGUCCCGGGAGGUGCCCUGGGCCCGGGGACCUCACAGGCAGGACGGCGACACUAAUGCAGGGAGAGGGAGUCUGGCCCCAGCUUUUCCUAUCAGAGGCGAUUUUCCUUCACCAGGGGAUGGGCAGGAAAGAGGCAGGGGCCCCAGAAGCUUCUGUCCCUCAUGCCUGAGGGCACGGGGGACACUUGGAGGCUGCUGUCACCACUGUGCGUCCAAGGCCAUGCUCUCUGCGGGUCAGUGCCUGAGUCUCGCCUCCCUGCUGGUCCCUGAAGCCCCCUCAGAAGCCCUGCCUGUCACGUCGGCAUUUGUGAGACCUACCCUGUAACGCCUGCCCCUCUCAGCCCAACAUCAGCUUCCUCUUUCUCCCUUGCUGUAGACAGGCUGGAUUCCAGUGUUGGGACAGCCAUCUCCAGAAACCUGACUUAAGAGAGUAAGAUGCAAAUCGUGCCUGUAUCCAGUGGCUUCGGUGGGUGCAGGGAGUCUUGGGCACAGCCAGCUCAGCUGUCUGUGGUAUGAGCAGGAACAGGUGCCACUCCUGCUCAGGGGACCCUGCCCUACACCAGGCUGUUCCGUCCCCCUGGAGGACAUGGGGCCAGGUCUGGAGGCAUUUUGGGUUGUCACAGCUGGGGGCUGUUCCUCGGCUUCAGCGGGUGGAAGCCUCAGAUGCUGUUCAACAUCUUCUGGACACGGGAGGCCCCGACAGAGAGAAGCGUCCACCCGCAAGUCCACAGUCUGAGGUCUCCCCUCAGAGACCCUGCCCUGCACACCCACCUCCAGCCAAAGGUCCUGCCUGCCCCAGGGCUCAGGGGAACCUUGCCGGUCUGUGGAACAGGAGAGGGGACUCUCGCCAGCUGCACCACCCUGCACGUAGUAGGUGUGCGGUAAACAUCCACCAGGGAGGCUCCAUUCAAGGCUGGCAGAUGGGGCGGUCCAUCCCUAGGGCAGGUGACAGAAGGGAAAAGGCUGCCUGCUGGCCCCCGAGCCAGGUAGCACAUGCUUGUGCCUCAGUUUCCCCUCCUGUAAAGUGAGGCGCUGGAUCCAGGUUCUGUCUACUGGGCUCUGCAGCUUGGACGCUCCUAAGACCAAGCGACCCACCCUGGGGAGGGCAGCUAUGGCUUUGGAAUAGCUGUCCAGGCCCGGGUGCCUCCAAGACGGCCACCACACCCUGCCUGUGCUGCAGGGGUGCAGGGGUAAGGGGCAAGACUCCAGAGGCCUCCUCUCUGCAUCUCCUUGUCUUCAGUGGCCGGAGGUGAGGCCUGAGCUCAGGGGAGGGGCUUCUGCCACGAACCCUAUGGCGGGGCACAGCACACUUUUCCCAGGGAGGACCCCUGGGCCCCCUGCAUUAUCCCCAGCGGAGUGUGGGGUCACCUUCCAAGAGCGACAUUGAGAAGCUCCAGCUCUAGGAGUGUGCAGACUCUUAACCAGGCAGGCCCAGGCCCUGGGGCACACAAAGGCGGGGCCUGCUCUCCCCAGCUGCCCCUGCCAAUGGGGGCUGGACUGUCCUACCCUCCUCCCUUCUACCUCCCCACUGUCUUCCCUCUCCACUGUCACCACUGCCUCCCUCUUCCACUGUCCUCCAUGCACUGCCCUCCCUCCACCUUCCCCCACCCCCACCACUCCCCAUGCUGUCCCCAGGCUCCCCCCGCUCUCCCCCCUCCCCACUGUCCCCCUCCCCAUGCUGUCCCCAGCUCACCCCGCUCUCCCCCCUCCCCACUGUCCCCCUCCCCAUGCUGUACCCAGCUCACCCCGCUCUCCCCUCUCCCCACUGUCCCCCCUCCCACUCCCCAUGCUGUCCCCAGCUCACCCUACAUGGACUUGGCGAUGUCCUUCCAUGGCUCACCGGUCUGAAUUUCCAUGAUGAGCCGGGCCUGCAGCUUUGCUCCCCUAUCCCUGCCCAGGCUGCAGCCAUCCAUGCAGGGAGCGAGCUCCAGCACCUGCGGAGUCCUUCCGUGGGGGCCUCUCCGUGCCACAGCAGCCAGGGACCUCAGGUGCCUGUGCAUGACACCACCGCCCAUCCUCAUCCUGAGCCAGCCUCUCAGGAUCAGGACUUGGUUUGGCGGCGUUAACCUUAGAGCCUGCAAGGGGCUUCCUCCUGGUGGGUCUGGCCGUAGCCUGGGGAGGCCACAGCUCCAGGCCACUCCAGACCUCCCUUCCUCUGGGCCUUCCAUGUGGUGGCAACCACCGCAGCUGUAAGGGAGGGAAAAUGGAGCGUUUGUUCUCGGGCUGGGCUGGGGUCUGGGGGAAGCCAUGGGCGUGAAGACUGGGGUAUUAUUUGAUGGAGAAGCGGCCACUCCUGGAGACCGGCGGCAAACACAGAAGCACAGCGUGGAAGGUGCUGGUGUCAGCCCACACGGGUGAUGGGGUCAGACUCAGGAGUCACACUCAGGAGUCACCAGGCUCAAAGGGCCCAGGCACCGCAAGUCCUGCUCAGCCCCAGACACAAUGCAUUCCUGUUGCCCUCGCCCUCAGCCAGGCCCCACGCAGGCCAGGGAGCACUGGCAAAGCUUGGCAACCCUCUGGGGGCCAGCCUUCAUCCAGGCCGAAGGUGGUCAGUGGCCCACCAUGGCCCAGGUAGAAAACUCACGGAUUAAGAUUUCAUGCCCGACUCCAAAGGCAAGAGACUUUAUUAUUUUAUUUUUUUUGAGCCAGAGUAUCGCUCUGUCACCUAGGCUGGAGUGCAAUCUCUGCUCAUUGCAACAUCUGCCUCCCGGACUCAAGCAAUUCUGCCUCAGCCUCCCAAGUAGCUGGGAUUACAGGUGUGCGCCACCAUGCCCAGGUAAUUGUUGUAUUUUUAGUAGAGACAGGGUUUCACCAUGUUGGUCAGGCUGGUUUCAAACUCCUGACCUCAAAUGAUCUGCCCACCUCGACCUCCCAAAGUGCUGGGAUUACAGGUGCGAGCCACCGCACCUGGCUACCAGACACUUCAGAGUUACAGGUUAGUUUUUCUUUUUCUUUUAUUUUUUUUUUUUGGCGGAGGUGCAGGGGGAGUUAAACAAACAAACAAAAUAAACAGGCCGGGUGCGGUGGCUCAUGCCUGUAAUCCCAGCACUUUAGGAGGCCUAGGUGGGUGGAUCACGAGAUCAGGGGUUCAAGACCAGCCUGGCCGAGAUGGUAAAACCCCGUCUCCACUAAAAAUACAAAAAUUGGCCAGGCACGGUGGCUCACACCUGUAAUCCCAGUACUUUGGGAGGCUGAGGUGGGCAGAUCACCUGAGGUCAGGAGUUCAAGACCAACCUGACCAACAUGGAGAAACCCCAUCUCUACUAAAAAUACAAAAUUAGCCAGGUGUGGUGGUGCAUGCCUGUAAUUCCAGCUACUCGGGAGGCUGAGGCAGGAGAAUUGCUUGAACCCAGGAGGCAGAGGUUGCAGUGGGCCAAGAUGGCGCCAUUGCACUCCAGCCUGGGAACAAGAGCGAAACUCUGACUAAAAAAGAAAGAAAGAAAGAAAAAAAUUAGUUGGGCACGGUGGCAGGCGCCUGUAAUCCCAGGUACUCAGGAGGCUGAGGCAGGAGAAUUGCUUGAACCCGGGAGGCAGAGGUCGCAGUGAGCCGAGAUUGCACCACUGCCCUCCAGCCUGGGUGACAGAGCAAGACUCCGUCUCAAAAAAAAAAAAAAAAAAAAUUGGAUACAUUGUAAUACCUCAAAUACUUGUAAGUGAAGCACCCCAGUUCCCAUAGAGCUGCCGCACUCAGAGGCUUCUGUAACCUGCCUGCUCCCAGCAUUCUAUUUAGGGUCUGGUAUGUCCAGAAUUUGCAGACACAGCAAUUCCUGCAGCAGCAGUGCACCAUGUGGAAGGGGCCCCAUGACCAGCCCACUGUGAGCUCACACGUGAUGACUGAGGCUUCUUCACACAGCAGGGCUCUGGGUGUGAUACCCAGGGCACACGCGUUUGCACAGGCACAGGCCACACAAGUUCUCACAUGCUCAGCCCCAUAAGCCGUGCUGGACAGGCAUGGCCAUUUACACCCAGGAUCCUGCUGAGAACAGCAACCAACUCACCACCCUCGCAUCAUGAUCCUUGCCACACAGGGGCUCUGGUGGCUUUGGUGGCCUGGGCUGUGGCUCUGCUGCCAGCCACCUUGAGUGAAGAUCCGGGUUCUCUGGGUGCUACUCAGCUGCUAUGUGGGGAGCUGGCCCCUGGGGUGAUGAGGGCCCUUCCCAACCCGCCCUCAGCCCUUGGACAGCCAGGAUCACCCGGGGCUGUCUGCAUACAGACUUCUCAGGGGAGUUCUCAGCUUGGACCCUUAUCUCCCCAGAAUCCUGGAACCUGCUCCUUCUGCUCUCGUGACUGACUGUGUUCUCUAUGCAACUUCCAAUAAAACCUCUUCAUUUGAAAGGAAAAAA